AGAGCUAAGUCUCCGGGCUCCUUUCACAUCUGCAGGAGCAGCCAGCCUGGGACCGCGCGGCGCGGGGCGCGCUCUCGCCUCUCCUGCACCCUCAGCCGGCGCGCUUCUCUUAUGGGCGUCUGCUGCAGUCUGGCUGCGGUCGAACUGAAAGCGGCGGCGGGAGACCAAACUUAGACCCCGCUGUGGACUAGAGAACUCAGAGAAGGCAGAGGGAGAGGGAGAGAGAGAGAGAGAAGGGACCCGAGGAGGAGGCUUCCAUCACGUCAUUGCAGGUAUUUAACCUGGAUAUGCCAGUUUUCUCCUGUAUGCACUGUUCCUGCCUAAGUCACAGAGUCAGUCUCUGUCCAUUCCAGCCCACAAGGAAACAAAGUGUCUACCAAUGGCUAUCGUUUCCAAUUGUUUGGAUUGAAGAAACUCACAUGACAAUUAUAUUUCAAGAGAAAUGAGAGCUAGCUGGGCACGGUGGCGGGCGCCUGUAAUCCCAGCUACUCAGGAGGCUGAGGCAGGAGAAUCGCUUGAACACAGGAGGCGGAGGUUGCAGUGAGCCGAGAUCACGCCAUUGCUCUCCAGUCUGGGCAACAAGAGCAAAACUGUCUCAAAAAAAAAAAAAGAAGAAGAAAAAGAAAAGAAAAGAAAAAUGAGAGCACUCAGAGCUGAGUCCACGUCAGGGAGCAGGCAGACGCCUUGCAGGAUGUUCUGGAAGCUUUCCCUGUCCUUGUUCCUGGUGGCGGUGCUGGUGAAGGUGGCGGAAGCCCGGAAGAACCGGCCGGCGGGCGCCAUCCCCUCGCCUUACAAGGACGGCAGCAGCAACAACUCGGAGAGAUGGCAGCACCAGAUCAAGGAGGUGCUGGCCUCCAGCCAGGAGGCCCUGGUGGUCACCGAGCGCAAGUACCUCAAGAGUGACUGGUGCAAGACGCAGCCGCUGCGGCAGACGGUGAGCGAGGAGGGCUGCCGGAGCCGCACCAUCCUCAACCGCUUCUGCUACGGCCAGUGCAACUCCUUCUACAUCCCGCGGCACGUGAAGAAGGAGGAGGAGUCCUUCCAGUCCUGCGCCUUCUGCAAGCCCCAGCGCGUCACCUCCGUCCUCGUGGAGCUCGAGUGCCCCGGCCUGGACCCACCCUUCCGACUCAAGAAAAUCCAGAAGGUGAAGCAGUGCCGGUGCAUGUCCGUGAACCUGAGCGACUCGGACAAGCAGUGAGCGCCGGGCCGGACGCAGCUCAGCCCCGCGCGCGCCCGGCCGCUGGGUGGCGCCGCCGCCGCCUCUGUCCCUGCCCUCCGAGCCCACUGUCACGCUGCCUGGUGUUCCCCCUCAGCAGCAAGCACUUCUCUUAGGGCUGACGGUGUCCUUGUCACAGACGUGGAUCGCAAGUGGAGCUUUUGCUGAUGUGUUCCUGACCGACCCCGGGUCCCACCUGUGCCCCCUAAACCAGGCGGUGGAUCAGGCCCGAAGGAAAAUGCUGGAAAACCACCACCGCCACCCAGCAGUCAGAGAGGACCUUUCGAGGUGAUGCACUGUAAAUCCGGCAUUGAUGUUUCCACCAUGUGGAAAAGCAAGGAUUUCCCUGGCCCCGCCCUGCACUCCAGCUCGCCCCUUUCCCGCGCGAAGUGAAGGAUGCGUCACUUUUCUGAGCGGCCCCUCAGACCUCUCCUGCUGGUCCCUGGACCUCUGGCUGGGAGCGCUCAUUCUUGUGACUGGCAGGCUGCCCUCGGUCGCUGCUGUGAUGAGGAUAUGUGCAACCUCCAUAAAUAUGUCGGUGGACGGGGCGUCUCCUAAUAAACCUGAUACCAAGAAGACAACUUGAGCCACUUGGAUCCCGAAGUGGGCUUCCCGGGAAACCUCGAGCAGAGCAGGCUACACAAUCCCCCAUCCUCAAGUCCCCACCGCCUCUUCUUCCUCACUGUCCCCGCCCCCUAUUUGUGGACUAAAGAUGAACUCUGGUGUGCAUGCUAUUAUUGCUGCAAUUAGAAUAUUAUCACACACAAAGGUCUCUAUAUUAACGCUGGUUUUAUAAGUGACCGUAUAUUGUAAAGAGCUGUUAAAAAGUAUUAUAGACCUAUUCAUGUAUUAUUUCACAUGUUUUGACUCUGGCUUGCAGCACCAUUCGGAGUAAGGAUGACAGCAGGCCCAGAAGGUGUCUUACUCAGAAAAAAAAAUGCCUGGUCAGCAAUUCACUGUCAUGCACCUAUUUUUAGAUUGGGCAGGGAGAUGGGAGGAGUCGUGAUUUUUACUUUGAAUACUAUUUCACUGACGUUACUAAGCAUUGCAGCACAAUGUAGAAAUUGGCUUGGGAUGGAUAGGUAUAGGGAAGGGCAUUCGUUGGGAAAUUGAUGACCGGAAACUAGAAAGCCCCUAUAAUGUGGAAUAUGCAUAUGUGGGGUGAAACCGUAUACUACUUUCACUGCCAUGACACUAGGCAAAAAAUAUUUCCUGUUAAAAGAAAGAGAAAAAGAGAGGGAUAUUGAAAAAUAUAAGGAGUUGAGUCGCUUUGUGGUAUAGAAGGGAGUAAGGAAUAAAAGAUAUAGAAUAGUAAUCUAGUUGAACUGUUCUGCACAAAACAUGCUUCCUUUUCAAAGAAUAGACUUCAAAAGGGACGAACAAACAUUAGGUCACCUUUUGUGUUUAUAAUGAAUUGUUGACGUUUCCAUGCUGUGGUCUCUUGAUAUACGGAAGUAGACGUAACUUAUUUUCCAGCGAAAUUAUAUACUUCUUCUGGGCUCCUUUGCUCAGUUGCCCCAGGAAGGCUUCCCUGUGAGUAAUGCUUAUGGAAUCUGACAAAUGUGAAUGAGCUGCCAUUGGUGGGAAUCAGUAAACUUUGAAAACCUUUCACUGAUGAUUCCCUGGUAAGUGCUCCUGUGAGGGGCCACUUCCCUAGUAUGUGAGAGAGACCCUCUGCAAGCCGCUGUGGGGACUUAGCUUCCUGAUACUAGGUAGUGAUGGUGGAUCUAGAGACAUUCACUUGAAGAGCAAGGAUUGGGGUGGGGUGGGUUGGUGAAUCUAUCUCAGGCCACUGCACUGCAAGGUGCAUUUCUGUCAUUUCUGCAACACCAUGAGACCUGAGCAAGAAUGUGCUGUGGCAGAGGGGGUCUUGGUUUCAUAAAUGGGUAUAUACAGCCUGAACUCAGGAGGCAGAAAUCAAAAGAAAUCCUUGAGGGCUGGAACCUGAGGAUAGAGCGAAAAUGGAGAGAAGGGUGUUCAAGGUCAGGAGUGAUUUUUGCAUUUGGUGGAAAACCUCAAGUCAGACUCAGUGGCAGAACAUGCAGCAGAAAAGCUGUGAAGGAAGGAAAUUUACGUGAUUGUAAUGGAGGCUAGGGGUGGAUUGGGAGGUGAGUGGAGGAGAGUCUCUGACCAGCUGCAGAGCCAACCCCUAUCAUUUUAUUAACAUGGAACCCACACAGAUAGGGGAGGGAUUAAGCUAAGAACUUACAGAAUGCAAACACGAGCACACUCUCUUCGAACCCAAUUGUGGGUGUAGCAAUGAAAGCAAUAUGAUAUGCUGCAGUGUGAAGCUCCUUCUGGGGUUAUCGUAUGUACAAAGUUUACCUUAUAAUGGCUCAAAUUGUAUUUAAUUUUUUUGUUUUGUUUAUAAAUGAAGAAAAGCUAUAAGUAUAAUGUAAUUAUUUUAUAGGUAUACUAUUAAAUUAUAGAACAAAUAAAGAUAAUCUAGGAUUAUAUGUGAUCCCGGUGUGACGUGCCAUAAAAGUGGAAUUUUUGACUUGUUGCAGUGAGCUGUGAAGCAGCACUAUGCGUUCAGAGAGUUUUUGUUCAACCAUGGUGAGUUCAACCUCUAGCUUAUGUCACAUGAUCUCCUUUGGGGUCUGGAAUCUUCUAAGAGAAAUAGAAUCAGGCAUCCAAGGAGCAGAAGUGAUGGAGGUGGCCCUCAAUCCUGGUCUUUGGAAGCUUCCAAGCCUCUUCCACAUCCCCUGCCAGCUGAAGACAGAGUAUUCUCACUGUGCUGGCUGAAGGAGAAACACUAAACAAGGAAACCUUGAGAAACUGCAGCAAUGGAAGUCCACUGUUAGUCUCUCCGUUAGCACCAGGGACACACUUGUUCUGAGUUUUGUUCAUUUUCACAUUUACUCCUCAUGAGUUCCAACAUUUCUUAAUUUAAAUAUUUCUUAGUUUAUAGCAUCUCCAUUUUUCUAUUAAUUGACUUAAUCUGCCAUUUAAGAAAACUCCGUAAUCAAUAAAAAAUAAAAUCCACAAUCAAACUGCACAUGGUUGAUCCACUGUGUAGGCUUCAAAGGAAUUAAACUCAACUUCCUAGGAAAUAAUUCAUCUUAGUUUAUUAAAUGGGACAGAAUAUUUCACUGCUAACGUAUUCUAACUCACUUGUUUUUGAAAUUGGCCAGAUGAUUUUUAAGUUAUAAAGUCAAUGAAAAUGACUUUUGCUAUUGUGUGAACAACUUAGAAUGUAUAUAUUCCCAGAAGGCUUAUUUAAUGAUUGACCUAUCACCACUGAUUAUUAAUGUCUGCAUGAAUGAUAACAAUAAGACCAAGUCAUCAAUAAUGCAAUGAAAAUUUUUUAAGUGAAAGCAAGUUUAUUAAGAAAGUAAAGGAAUAAAGAAUGCCUACUUCAUAGGCAGAGCAGCCUAA